ACUCUGGAAGCUGAGCCGGCGGCGGGAGGAGCUAGGGCUGGAGCCUCUCCAGCCUCCCGCGAAGGUAAAGCCGACUCCGGGCACUGGGCUCUGGGGCUCUGCCUUACUCCCUUCCCACGCCGUGGGGACUUUGUGGGGCUCAGGGCAGGGAAAACGGGGUGGUCUUGGCUGCUGCAGCCUGCAGCUGCUAAGGAAGCAGAUUACCCUUCCCCCAGGCUGCUGGUCUGGUUCCUUUCGUUGGACGCCCCCCCGGCUUUGAGUGACAUUAGCUCAGGGCGCUGCCCUGUCCAGCCCCACCCCUUUUUUUUGCUUGUUUUAUACCUAGUACGCUCCUCCACUCGCCUUAACAUAUCCUUACCCCACAGGCUCUUCAUUCCCUUGUGGGUUCCGCCCUCGGGAUUCCCUUCCAGUCUCCUAGUCUGAGCACCCUUCCUGCUGGAUGCCGGCAACUCUUGUUUCCUUGGGUCAGCGACCCUCCUUCCGAACAAGUCCUGCAGACUGACUUUCUUUGCUUUGUUUCGUUUUGUUAGGAAAUGAGCAUCCGCGUCGUCUGUUCUCCAGUACUUUUUCUAAAAUCAUUUUCUCCCCUAAGGCUUUUCCUUCCUGCAAGGCAGCUUAUUCACGUGGCCUUUCCUCCGCUGCUGUGAUUUUAUCUUUGAAUGUGGCCUUUGGAGUGGGUAAAGUAGGACUUAGACGCUCAGUGAAGUGGCUGUUAAUCACUUGAUACUUAACUAUGUUUAAGAGUGCCUUCCCUUAAAUUUUCUCCUUUUGUAGCGUGUUCCGUUAACCACGUUUGUCUUAAGAUUGUUUCCUGUGUCCGUUGCUUAGAGGGGGGAAAAAAGUAAAGAUUUCACCCUAAUGUGGCGGUGGUCUCCCAAAGUAAUUAUUUCUCAUUUUCCCUCUGCUUUUCCCUUUUACGUUAUUCUGAUUUCCCUCAAAAAGGAGGUUCUGUACCUGAUGCUGUUGCGUCCUCUAUGAAGGGCUUUAUAGUGUACAGUUAUGUUGAGCCUUUUGUAAUACAGUGUCUUGGGGAAAAAAGUAGAAGUUCAGAACCUGCCCCCAGUAAUUCUUUCUUACUAUAUUUUCUUUCUCAGUUUAUGGACUUGAUAGGUUUCUAGGUUUGAAACUACUGCCUGCAGGGAAAAUUACAGUGAUAAGGUUUUAUAAUAUAUUACCAGUACUUUGAGUUUAUGGGAGUAUGAAACAGAAUUUGCCUUAAAAAAAUAAAUUUAUAGAAACCACUUGUCAGAAAUUCGGUAUCCAGAACACAGUUCUUUGAUUUUUGGAAAGUACUUUAUUGGCUUAUCUAUCAUAUAACGUAAAACCUUGUUCACAUUUUGUGUAAUGUGAAACGCUUUUUAAGCUACUAUAUCUCAGACUUGGCUUGUGCUGUUAGUAUCACAAUGCAUUCAGGCAACACACGUCCUUGUGUAGAAAUUAUUACAUUAUACUCCUUGUUUGAAAACAGGAAGUAGAACAUAUUAAGGGAGGAAAAGAGGAGUCAGAGGAUUAUUAAGAAAUAAGAAUGUAAAGAACCUUAAGGCUAGAGUUCAGUUCAUGGAAAAUAUCAGCAUUUGUAUUCCACUGAGAGGCAAUGAAUAUUCCUCUUUUUCUAAAGUGGUAGUAAUAAAUAGUCUAAAAUAUAUUAAUGUUAUAUAUUGUUAACAAGCUUAGUUGUAAACAAAAUACUUAAGCUAAAAAAUAAAAUAUUAAUAAGUGAAUGAAUUGUUUGGAAUAAUUUAACUUUAUCCACAAAUAAAUAGAAGAUGGUUGCCUUGCCCAGGUGGACUGUAACAAUACUGGCUUUAUUAAAUUUGUUAAAAGGUUGAUAGUGGAGUCCGGUUCUCAAUAGGUCCCAAAUUAGGGUUGAAAUUGAAAAGAUGUGUUUUAACUAAUUUGGCUUCAUUCCUCAACCAGUUCUGUUUACACAGGUGAAUAUGAGGUUUCUGCUACACAUACCUUUCCCCUGCUUCUGAUUGAGGUACUUUAAAUUAGUAAUUGAAACAAGGCUGUGCAGAUAAACUGCAGCACAAAUUUGGUUGCUACAAAUAGGUUUUGGCCUAAAUGUUCACUGUAAAACAUGGCAGUAGUUAAAGGGGAGUUAUUAAUAUUUUGAAAGAGUUCCUUGAGUCAGUGUUUCUCAACUUUAUUAGACCCAAUAAAGGCUCCCUUUUUAUAAAAAAUAAUUAGUAACACCUUCUUUGCUAUCUUUAGUUUAUAAAUAAUGUAACUACCUCUGGCUUUGGCCCUGAGACAAAAAAAGAAGCUUUGCUCUCACUUCUGCAACAAAAAAAGACCUACACUACAAAUUCAUGACUUUUUUGAAAUCUAUUAAAGAGCUGAGUCCACAGAGCAAAACCACUGGCUGAAAAUUUGAGAGACAGUGCUUACAGAGAGUAGAUGUCAAUUUCUGUUUACCGUCUUCAGACACAACUGGACAAAAAGCAUGAUGAAAGCUGAAUGCACAAUCUUGCAAACUCUUAUCCACAAACCUCCCUGGGUCUACUAGAAAAGACUGGAAAGAACCCUGGGUGAGUCUGCUGUGCAGAUUGAGAGGGAGAGGAACAGCAACAGAACUUUUAAGAGGGUCAAGAAACUGCUGUGAUUCUUCCCCUCUGCCUCUUCUAUGGAAAAAAGCUUUAAUCUCUGGGGAGAAGGGUAUCUCUGUUGGCCCCAUUGGUGAACAUUCAGGGGGUAGAUGAGAAGUGGGAGAGAAUCUUAUGCCUGGAGGAGGGGCCCUGAGCCCAAAACUGCAGUCGGGAGUGGUCAACAGAACCGAGAGUGCUGCCCUCCUGAGAUUCAGGAACACAGUGUUUGACUUAGACUUAAUCAGAACAUCAGACUGUAUCCCCCACCCCCAACCCCCUGCCACCAAGCUAAGAAGCUUUCAGUAACAAGUAACCCACAAAAUACUACUAGGAAAGGAACAAGAUUAUGCAAAGAGGCACAACACAAAGAAUCAAACAGGCAUUGCUCUAGUAAACCAUCGCCCACCAGAGAGACAAACUGUUCUGCAGAUUCAUGAAGGCUGUAAUACACUGAGGAUAACUAUGGCAAAAACAAAUCAUAAACUAAGUCCAACUCCUAACCAGAUUAACACAAACCCUUCACCAAAGGCCUCACAAAGAACAGGCGUGCUCAUUUCCAGUCAUAAAAAUUACCUCAAUCUCUACUCCUACACAACAUGUCCAGCUUUUAACCAAAAAUUAUGAGGCCCAUGAAAAAAACUCCCAAGAGAAAGAGCAGUCAUCAUUAUACAUUUUUUAAAAAGAUAGGAGCUUAAAAAGAACUGUUUUGUACAUGUUAAAUACUAUAAUAAUGACAUUUUGCCUUGAAAAAGUUUGAGCAAACAAUGCAGUGAGCAUUGGAUGGAGUUAUAGUUUCUGAAUUACUGUGAAGUAGUAGAAGGAAAAAAAGUUAUAAGAUGGAGUGGAAAAUUAGUAACAUAUAUGUGAAUGUAUGUGGUUCAUUGACCACCUGAAGUGUGUGUGUGUAUUUUGUGAAUUCCUGCAUGACUCAGUUGGGUACAAUUUUCUGCGUUCACUUAGUGUUGGGACAGAAUCACUAUAAGCAAAUGUGACAUUUUCAUUAUGCUCAAAUUGUUCAGUAAUACACCAAUCCUGUUAAAAUUCACAUGAUCAAGAAAGCAUUAUAGCAGAAUUGACUAUAUGCAUUUCAAUAUGUAAAUAGUUAAGUAUGAUUAUACCAAAAUACACAAAGGACGUGUCAGAGGCUUGUAUCUUUACAUGGAAUCAUUUUGAGAUUUUUUUUGUGUGUGUGAGAGACAAUCUUGCUCUGUCACCCAGGCUGGAGUGCAGUGGCACGAUCUUGGCUCACUGCAACCUCUGCCUCAGCCUCCUGAGUAGCUGGGACUACAGGCGCUUGCCACCAUGCUGGGCUGAUUUUUUUUUUUUUCUGUAUUUUUAGGAGACAGAGUUUCACCAUGUUGCCCAGGCUGGUCUCGAACUCCUGACCUCAAGUGAUCCACCCACCCAGGCCUCCCAAAGUGCUGGGAUUACAGGUUUGAGCACAAAAUGAACAUAAUUAGGGAAAAUAAGGAUCUGGCAUGUUUCUACACAACAAAACAUUCAUGGAGGGGGAAGUAUAAGCGUGUCUUUUCAGUUGGAACUCAUGCGAUUACUACAUAUAAUCCCAAUACCUUAGAAGUAACAAAUCAGUGGCCUUAUGGAGACAUUUGCAGCAUCAGCCCUGUUGGAAAAGGACAAGGAACGGAGUUCAACCUCACAUUUCGUAAAGGCAGUGGAAAAAAGUCAGAAACUUUAAAAUUUUCUACAGAGCACAGAACAGAACUUCUUACAGAAGCAUUGAGAUUUAGAACUGAUUUUUCAGAGGGAAAAAUCACAGGAAGGAGAUACAACUGCUAUAAGCAUCACUGGAGUGACUCAAGAAAACCUGUAAUUUUGGAAGUAACUCCAGGAGGCUUUGACCAAAUUAAUCCUGCAACCAACAGAGUACUCUGUUCCUAUGACUAUAGAAAUAUUGAAGGAUUUGUAGAUCUCUCAGAUUAUCAAGGAGGAUUUUGUAUACUUUAUGGAGGAUUUAGUAGAUUGCAUUUAUUUGCGUCAGAGCAAAGAGAAGAGAUUAUUAAAAGUGCAAUAGACCAUGCUGGUAACUACAUAGGUAUUUCAUUGCGGAUCAGGAAAGAGCCUUUAGAAUUCGAGCAAUAUUUGAAUCUUCGCUUUGGAAAAUACAGCACUGAUGAAUCCAUCACAUCUUUAGCAGAGUUUGUAGUCCAAAAAAUAUCACCUAGACAUUCGGAGCCUGUUAAAAGAGUUCUAGCACUUACAGAAACAUGUUUAGUAGAACGUGAUCCGGCAACCUAUAAUAUUGCAACAUUGAAGCCUUUAGGAGAAGUAUUUGCGUUGGUCUGUGACUCAGAAAAUCCACAACUUUUUACCAUUGAAUUUAUAAAAGGGCAAGUACGGAAAUAUUCUUCAACAGAGAGAGAUUCCUUAUUAGCAAGUUUGCUGGAUGGAGUAAGAGCCUCUGGUAAUAGAGAUGUUUGUGUAAAAAUGACACCAACCCAUAAAGGUCAGCGAUGGGGGUUACUCAGCAUGCCUGUUGAUGAGGAAGUAGAGAGCCUUCACCUCAGGUUCUUAGCUACGCCUCCAAAUGGCAACUUUGCAGAUGCUGUAUUCAGGUUCAAUGCUAAUAUUUCAUACAGUGGAGUCCUACAUGCAGUAACACAAGAUGGUCUCUUCUCAGAAAACAAAGAAAAACUGAUCAAUAAUGCCAUAACAGCAUUACUGUCCCAAGAAGGGGAUGUCGUUGCUUCAAAUGCGGAACUUGAGAGUCAGUUCCAGGCUGUGAGGAGGCUUGUGGCAUCCAAAGCUGGUUUCCUGGCUUUCACUCAGCUUCCAAAGUUUCGCGAGCGUCUAGGGGUGAAGGUAGUAAAAGCACUCAAAAGAAGCAACAACGGAAUAAUCCAUGCAGCAGUUGAUAUGCUUUGUGCCCUUAUGUGUCCCAUGCAUGAUGACUAUGACUUAAGACAAGAACAGUUGAACAAAGCUUCUCUUCUCUCGUCAAAGAAGUUUCUGGAAAACUUACUGGAGAAAUUUAAUUCCCAUGUGGAUCAUGGGACUGGUGCCCUAGUUAUUAGUUCGCUCUUGGACUUCCUUACCUUUGCCCUCUGUGCUCCAUAUAGUGAGACAACUGAAGGGCAGCAGUUUGAUAUGCUCUUGGAGAUGGUAGCAUCCAAUGGAAGAACCCUUUUUAAACUUUUUCAGCAUCCUUCCAUGGCAAUAAUAAAAGGAGCUGGGUUGGUUAUGAAGGCAAUAAUAGAGGAAGGUGAUAAAGAAAUUGCUACAAAAAUGCAGGAGCUUGCCCUAAGUGAAGGUGCCUUACCUCGACACUUGCAUACUGCGAUGUUUACAAUAAGCUCAGAUCAAAGGAUGCUUACAAAUAGACAGCUAAGUAGACAUUUAGUGGGACUCUGGACAGCUGAUAAUGCAACUGCAACAAACUUGUUGAAACGCAUUUUGCCGCCAGGCUUGCUGGCAUACUUGGAAAGCUCAGAUCUCGUACCUGAGAAGGAUGCUGAUCGGAUGCAUGUUAGAGACAAUGUGAAAAUAGCAAUGGAUCAGUAUGGAAAAUUUAAUAAAGUUCCAGAGUGGCAAAGACUAGCUGGAAAAGCUGCUAAAGAAGUUGAAAAAUUUGCCAAAGAAAAAGUGGAUCUUGUAUUGAUGCACUGGAGGGAUAGGAUGGGCAUUGCUCAAAAAGAGGACAAAAACAAUAUGAAUAUAAAUCAGAAGCCAGUGGUUCUUCGAAAGAGAAGACAAAGAAUAAAAAUAGAAGCAAAUUGGGAUCUCUUCUAUUAUAGGUUUGGUCAAGACCAUGCCAGGUCAAACCUUAUUUGGAAUUUCAAAACACGAGAAGAACUGAAAGAUACUCUUGAAUCUGAAAUGAGAGCAUUUAAUAUUGACAGAGAACUUGGAAGUGCAAAUGUGAUCUCCUGGAACCACCAUGAGUUUGAGGUUAAAUAUGAGUGCCUGGCAGAGGAAAUUAAAAUAGGAGACUAUUACCUGAGAUUACUAUUGGAGGAAGAUGAGAAUGAAGAAAGUGGAUCAAUUAAGAGAUCGUAUGAAUUUUUCAAUGAGCUUUAUCAUCGCUUCUUGCUCACCCCAAAAGUAAACAUGAAGUGUUUAUGUUUACAAGCCCUUGCUAUUGUUUAUGGCAGAUGUCACGAAGAAAUAGGACCUUUUACAGAUACCAGAUAUAUCAUUGGAAUGUUAGAGAGGUGCACAGAUAAACUUGAACGAGAUAGGUUGAUUCUCUUCCUUAACAAGUUGAUCCUUAAUAAGAAAAAUGUUAAGGAUCUCAUGGAUUCAAAUGGAAUAAGAAUCCUUGUGGACUUGCUUACCCUUGCACAUCUCCAUGUAAGCCGAGCUACAGUACCACUGCAAAGCAAUGUAAUUGAAGCUGCUCCAGAUAUGAAAAGAGAGAGUGAAAAGGAAUGGUAUUUUGGCAACGCAGACAAAGAAAGGAGUGGCCCGUAUGGAUUUCAUGAGAUGCAAGAAUUGUGGACCAAAGGAAUGUUAAAUGCAAAAACCAGAUGCUGGGCUCAAGGCAUGGAUGGAUGGCGACCACUUCAGUCCAUACCCCAGCUUAAGUGGUGUCUCUUAGCCAGUGGACAGGCUGUCCUGAAUGAAACUGACCUUGCUACCCUUAUAUUGAACAUGUUGAUCACAAUGUGUGGAUAUUUUCCAAGCAGGGAUCAAGACAAUGCCAUCAUUCGGCCUCUACCCAAAGUGAAAAGACUGCUGUCAGAUAGCACUUGCCUUCCCCAUAUUAUUCAGCUACUGCUGACCUUUGACCCUAUCCUUGUUGAGAAGGUUGCUAUUUUGUUAUACCAUAUCAUGCAAGAUAACCCACAGUUACCCCGCCUUUAUCUGAGUGGAGUAUUUUUCUUUAUCAUGAUGUACACAGGUUCCAAUGUGCUUCCUGUUGCUCGAUUUUUGAAAUACACACAUACCAAACAGGCUUUCAAGUCAGAAGAGACAAAAGGACAAGAUAUUUUUCAGAGAAGUAUACUUGGGCACAUUCUACCUGAAGCAAUGGUUUGUUACUUAGAAAAUUAUGAACCUGAAAAGUUUUCUGAGAUUUUUCUAGGAGAAUUUGAUACUCCAGAAGCAAUCUGGAGCAGUGAAAUGAGGCGCCUGAUGAUAGAGAAGAUUGCUGCCCAUCUCGCGGAUUUCACACCUCGUCUUCAGAGUAACACAAGAGCACUUUAUCAGUAUUGCCCCAUUCCUAUAAUCAACUAUCCACAACUCGAAAAUGAACUAUUUUGUAAUAUUUAUUACCUCAAACAACUGUGUGAUACACUCCGGUUUCCAGAUUGGCCAAUUAAAGACCCGGUUAAGCUUCUAAAAGAUACCCUUGAUGCCUGGAAGAAAGAAGUAGAAAAGAAGCCACCUAUGAUGUCAAUAGAUGAUGCUUAUGAAGUGCUUAAUCUGCCUCAAGGACAGGGACCGCAUGAUGAGAGCAAGAUUAGGAAAGCUUACUUCAGACUUGCACAAAAGUACCACCCUGAUAAGAAUCCAGAAGGGAGGGACAUGUUUGAAAAAGUAAAUAAAGCAUAUGAAUUUUUAUGUACCAAAUCAGCAAAAAUAGUGGAUGGGCCAGAUCCAGAGAAUAUAAUUUUAAUUCUAAAAACACAGAGCAUCCUCUUCAACCGUCAUAAAGAAGAUUUACAGCCUUAUAAAUAUGCAGGAUACCCCAUGCUUAUUCGGACUAUAACAAUGGAAACUUCAGAUGACCUCCUUUUCUCAAAAGAAUCACCAUUGUUGCCUGCGGCUACAGAGCUAGCUUUCCAUACUGUCAACUGUUCAGCCCUCAAUGCUGAAGAGCUCAGAAGAGAGAAUGGACUAGAGGUGUUACAAGAGGCAUUUAGUCGCUGUGUGGCUGUCUUGACUCGUGCUAGUAAACCAAGUGACAUGUCAGUACAGGUGUGUGGAUACAUAAGUAAAUGCUACAGUGUGGCUGCUCAGUUUGAGGAAUGCCGAGAGAAGAUCACGGAAAUGCCUAGCAUCAUCAAGGAUCUCUGUCGGGUACUAUAUUUUGGCAAGAGUAUUCCCCGCGUAGCUGCUCUUGGGGUAGAAUGUGUCAGUUCUUUUGCUGUGGAUUUCUGGCUACAGACACACCUAUUUCAGGCUGGAAUUUUGUGGUAUCUCCUUGGUUUUCUGUUUAAUUAUGACUACACACUAGAAGAGAGUGGCAUUCAGAAAAGUGAAGAAACAAACCAGCAGGAGGUAGCAAACAGCCUUGCCAAACUGAGUGUCCAUGCUCUGAGUCGCCUUGGAGGGUAUUUGGCUGAAGAACAAGCAACUCCAGAAAAUCCAACCAUAAGGAAAAGCUUAGCUGGCAUGCUGACACCCUAUGUUGCUAGAAAACUUGCUGUGGCUAGUGUGACUGAGAUUUUGAAGAUGCUUAACAGCAACACAGAAAGUCCAUAUUUGAUAUGGAACAAUUCUACAAGAGCAGAAUUACUUGAAUUUCUUGAAUCCCAACAAGAAAACAUGAUUAAAAAAGGUGAUUGUGACAAAACUUAUGGAUCAGAAUUUGUCUACAGUGAUCAUGCCAAAGAACUUAUUGUAGGGGAGAUUUUUGUUAGGGUGUAUAAUGAAGUUCCUACUUUCCAACUGGAGGUUCCAAAAGCAUUUGCUGCAAGUCUCUUGGAUUAUAUAGGCUCGCAGGCCCAAUACUUGCACACAUUCAUGGCCAUCACACACGCGGCAAAAGUGGAGUCAGAGCAACAUGGAGAUCGCUUACCGAGAGUAGAAAUGGCUUUGGAGGCUCUGAGAAAUGUCAUAAAAUACAAUCCAGGUUCUGAGAGUGAAUGCAUUGGGCACUUUAAGUUGAUAUUUUCUCUUCUCCGAGUUCAUGGAGCUGGUCAAGUGCAGCAGUUGGCUUUAGAGGUUGUGAAUAUAGUGACAUCUAACCAAGACUGUGUCAACAAUAUUGCUGAAUCAAUGGUUUUGUCCAGUUUAUUGGCUCUUCUACAUUCAUUGCCAUCAAGUCGUCAGCUUGUUCUGGAAACUCUUUAUGCUUUGACAUCGAGUACAAAAAUAAUCAAAGAAGCAAUGGCAAAGGGUGCUUUGAUCUAUUUACUGGAUAUGUUCUGCAAUUCAACACAUCCACAGGUUCGAGCCCAAACAGCAGAACUUUUUGCCAAAAUGACAGCAGAUAAACUGAUAGGUCCAAAGGUUCGAAUUACGUUAAUGAAAUUUCUACCAAGCGUUUUCAUGGAUGCUAUGAGAGACAAUCCUGAAGCUGCUGUACAUAUUUUUGAAGGAACUCAUGAAAAUCCUGAGUUAAUUUGGAAUGAUAAUUCCAGAGAUAAAGUGUCCACAACAGUUAGGGAAAUGAUGCUAGAGCACUUUAAAAAUCAGCAGGACAACCCUGAGGCAAACUGGAAGUUGCCUGAAGAUUUUGCUGUGGUGUUUGGAGAAGCAGAGGGUGAACUUGCUGUUGGAGGAGUCUUCUUGAGGAUCUUUAUUGCACAACCAGCCUGGGUUCUAAGAAAGCCUAGAGAAUUUCUUAUUGCCCUGUUAGAAAAAUUAACUGAGCUCCUAGAGAAGAACAAUCCUCAUGGAGAAACUCUGGAAACCUUGACAAUGGCAACAGUGUGUCUCUUCAGCGCACAACCUCAGCUGGCAGAUCAGGUCCCGCCAUUGGGCCAUCUUCCCAAAGUUAUCCAGGCAAUGAAUCAUAGGAACAAUGCCAUUCCUAAGAGUGCCAUUCGGGUUAUCCAUGCCUUGUCUGAAAAUGAGCUGUGUGUUCGAGCCAUGGCAUCUUUAGAGACCAUUGGCCCACUGAUGAAUGGAAUGAAAAAGCGAGCAGAUACUGUUGGUCUAGCCUGUGAAGCAAUUAAUCGAAUGUUUCAGAAGGAGCAGAGUGAAUUAGUAGCACAAGCCCUGAAAGCAGAUUUGGUUCCAUACCUCUUAAAAUUACUCGAAGGCAUUGGCCUUGAAAACCUGGACAGCCCAGCAGCCACUAAGGCUCAGAUUGUUAAAGCUCUCAAGGCAAUGACUCGAAGUUUGCAGUAUGGAGAACAGGUGAAUGAAAUCCUGUGCCGUUCUUCAGUCUGGAGUGCCUUCAAAGAUCAGAAACAUGAUUUGUUCAUUUCUGAGUCACAAACAGCAGGAUACCUCACAGGACCUGGAGUUGCUGGCUACCUUACCGCAGGUACAUCUACAUCAGUCAUGUCUAACCUGCCACCUCCUGUAGACCAUGAGGCAGGCGACCUUGGCUAUCAGACUUGAAAUAUUCACGAGAGACAAUAAACGCUGAAAGGCCAGUGCCAAGUCCACAUUCCUCCAGCUGAUACGUUGAAGCAAACUCUUACUGCCUUUCUCCUGGUUUCAUGACAGUGUUAUUCCUUUUUCUAUAAAUAUAUUUUUAGGAAAAAAAGUCAGUGAUCCUAAUUGUAUCACAUUAUAAGAAAGCACUCUGUGGAUCAACAUAAGUGGGUACACAAGAAUUUUUUUUUUCUUGGUGUAUGUAAGCACAUUUGUUCCUUUAUAUCUGUUUACAAAACUGUGAAUCAAAAAGACAAAACUUUCUUCCUAGUUUUUGUAAUUUUUUUUUUGAACUAGCAUGACUGUAGGGUUGAGCUACAGUCAACAAAAAUUGGGCUAAGUCACUUUUCCCCAGGAAAGAAUAUUUCCCUCUCCUGCAUCAAGUCUGCGUGGCCAUCCUCCCCCCACCAUCCAAGACUAUUAGGUUUUGUCCCUGCACCCUUCACUGGCAUCCUCAAUCAUUAACCUUCUGAAAGCUCACAGUACACAUUAGUAUGUAUAACUGGCUUUACCAAAUUGAAUGAAAAGGAGCUUGUGCAAAAAAAUUUAAAAAUGGAUGUCAAGAUGUUAUGUAAAAGAUGAGUGUAAUUGUGAAAUGUUCUAUACACUAUCAAAUAUAUAAAGCUUUCUAUAUUGAAUGUACAUUAUACAGAUCAUUCAUAUGUGUACAUAAAAUUUUAAAAAUAAAGGGAAUUGACUGCUUUGUUAAUGAGA